CACAAUGGACAAUGGCAACUGCCCACACACUCCCAUGGAGGGGAAGGGGAUGAGUGCAGGGAACCCCGACCCCACCCGGGAGACCUGCAAGCCUGCAGACACUCCCCUCCCGCCCCCACUGAACCCUUGACCCCUGCCCUGCAGCCCCCGCAGCUUGCUGUUUGCCCACUCUAUUUGCCCAGCCCCAGGGACAGAGCUGAUCCUUGAACUCUUAAGUUCCACAUUGCCAGGACCAGUGAGCAGCAACAGGGCCGGGGCUGGGCUUAUCAGCCUCCCAGCCCAGACCCUGGCUGCAGACAUAAAUAGGCCCUGCAAGAGCUGGCUGCUUAGAGACUGCGAGAAGGAGGUCCCCCACGGCCCUUCAGGAUGAAAGCUGCGGUGCUGACCUUGGCCGUGCUCUUCCUGACGGAGCCCCUGGGAUCGAGUGAAGGACCUGGCCACUGUGUACGUGGAUGUGCUCAAAGACAGCGGCAGAGACUAUGUGUCCCAGUUUGAAGGCUCCGCCUUGGGAAAACAGCUAAACCUAAAGCUCCUUGACAACUGGGACAGCGUGACCUCCACCUUCAGCAAGCUGCGCGAACAGCUCGGCCCUGUGACCCAGGAGUUCUGGGAUAACCUGGAAAAGGAGACAGAGGGCCUGAGGCAGGAGAUGAGCAAGGAUCUGGAGGAGGUGAAGGCCAAGGUGCAGCCCUACCUGGACGACUUCCAGAAGAAGUGGCAGGAGGAGAUGGAGCUCUACCGCCAGAAGGUGGAGCCGCUGCGCGCAGAGCUCCAAGAGGGCGCGCGCCAGAAGCUGCACGAGCUGCAAGAGAAGCUGAGCCCACUGGGCGAGGAGAUGCGCGACCGCGCGCGCGCCCAUGUGGACGCGCUGCGCACGCAUCUGGCCCCCUACAGCGACGAGCUGCGCCAGCGCUUGGCCGCGCGCCUUGAGGCUCUCAAGGAGAACGGCGGCGCCAGACUGGCCGAGUACCACGCCAAGGCCACCGAGCAUCUGAGCACGCUCAGCGAGAAGGCCAAGCCCGCGCUCGAGGACCUCCGCCAAGGCCUGCUGCCCGUGCUGGAGAGCUUCAAGGUCAGCUUCCUGAGCGCUCUCGAGGAGUACACUAAGAAGCUCAACACCCAGUGAGGCGCCCGCCGCCGCCCCCCUUCCCGGUGCUCAGAAUAAACGUUUCCAAAGUGGGAA